GAACAUGGAUGCCUCGCUUUUCAGAGACUCGCGUUCUUGGAACUUACACCCUUUUGGGUUUGCUAUUUUUACCCACCCUGAGCCUUCCGGUCUCCAUGGCGACGCCUCCAAACAGCAGAUUCCAGGCGGCAAUGACGUCAUCUCUCCCUUUCCUGCCGCCCAGGCCUUGGAGAGAUCCAAGGCCUGUGGGCCACGGCUGCGCCUCUCCUGACUCCAGCUUGCCCGUCUGUCCUUGGGGGCAGCGUCCUUCCUUCUCUCGGCCCCAGACGCAGCUGCAUCCUGGAGUCCUUCUGAGAAAUGUGGGACCUGCCCCAGCUCCACCCCAGGGGCAGCGAGGGAGGCGUUGGAUGGAGCCACCCCACGGCUCCUCUGUGAAGGUCUGCACGUCACUCAGAAAGUUGAAGCAAACCAAGCAGGGUUGGAGCCCACAGUUCACAGCCGGCUGCACAGGGGAUGCACCAAGCACAGUUUCCUAUGACAAGUGGAAACCUGUGCGCCACAGGUGAGCUGGGUCCUGGAAGGUGCAGGGACCAGGCAGCAUCUCAUCUCAGGACAUCAAGGGCUGUCCCCAGCCAGCAGAUUUCCCAUAAAAACGUGCUGAACUGGGGACAAAGCUGAUUCUACAGAGCCGAGAAGCCAGACCUUCCCUGGGGACUCCCGAGGGGGUCCCAGCCACCCUCUCCACCUGCAGAGGUUUCCUGGCCCACUUGGAGGACCUUGGGGGAUCCUCCAAGGGCCCCCUUCCAGCUCUUGGCCCAUGGGGGAGCCUCUUCCUCAGCUCCGGGUGUGGUGGACAGGAGACCGAGGGCUCCCCGCACCCAGCUGGGCUCAGCGUUUUCAAGCUGAACUUGGUGCGUGGCGGCUUGGAAAGCCGGGAGCCUGCUGCGUGUCUCCUGGGGCUGCUGUGAAAAAAUGACCACACACUGGGAGCCUAAAACGAGUGACAUGUAUAUUCUCACAGUUCAGGCAGCUGGUGUCCAAAAUCAGUGGUUGGGAGGGUGGAGCUCCGCCUAAAGGCUCUGGGUGGCUGCUGCCUGCCCCUUCCAGCCCCGGGCCCCCGGCAUUCCCUGGCGUGCAGCUGCUCCACCCCCAACCCCAAAGCCUCCUUCCUGUGUCUCUGUGUCCAAAUUUUCCUUACCUUUUUUUUUUUUUUUUUGAGAUAGAGUUUUGCUCUUGUCGCCCAGGCUGGAGUGCAACAGCACGAUCUCGGCCUAUCGCAACCUCCGCCUCCUGGGUUCAAGCGAUUCUCCUGCCUCAGCCUCCUAAGUAGCUGGGAUUACAGGUGCCCACCACCACACCCAGCUAAUUUUGUAUCUUUAGUAGAGAUGGGGUUUCACGAUGUCUUUCAGGCUGGUCUCGAACUCCUGACCUCACAUGAUCCACCUGCCUCGGCCUCCCAAAGUGCUGAAAUUACAGGCAUGAGCCACAGCACCUGGCCAAUUUUCCUUUUCUUUCUCUCUCUCUUUUUUUUUUGAGACGGAGUCUUGCUCUGUUGCCCAGGCUGGAGUAAAAUGGCACAAUCUUGGCUCACUGCAACCUCUGCCUUCUGGGUUCAAGCGAUUCUCCUGCCUCAGCCUCCCGAGUAGCUGAGACUACAGGCGCCCACCACCACACCCAGCUAAUUUUUGUGUUUUUUAGUAGAGACGGGGUUUCACUAUGUUGGCCAGGCUGGUCUAGAACUCCUGACCUCAAGUGAUCUGCCCGCCUCGGCCUCCCAAAGUGCUGGGAUUGCAGGCGUGAGACACUGCACCCGGACAAUUUUCCUUUUCUUACAAGAACACUGCUCACACUGCAUUCAGGGCCAACCCUAACCCAGUAUCGCCUCAUCCUGGUUUGAUUAUAUCGGCACAGACCUUGCUUCCGAGCGAGGCCACUUUCUCAGGUACUGGUGGACAUGAGUCUUCGGAGACGCUGCUCAACCCACAGUGCUCCUCCAGCUUGGUUUCUGUGACUUGCCUUCCCCAGAGGAGGGGUGCCCUGAGAGGUCUCCACUCCCUGACCGGCUCCUUGGUGCCGCGCACUCUGAGAGGCUUCCCAGGGAACAGAGCACACAGGACCGCCCUCCUGGGUAGACCAAUCAGCAUCUGAGCUCACAAUUUCCCAGCAGGGCAGUGGGGUGGAGAGAGAAGCCUGGGCUGGGCUGGGCUGGGCUGGGCUGGGGAAGCUUCUCCGGGCGGGGGGACGUCAGAGCAGGAUCUGGGGCUGAUAAAAGCCCGCCCCUGGGUGGGGGCUGAGUGGUGCGGAAGCUGAGCCCGACACGUGGGGAUGGAGGACAGGCUGUGGGAGGGUGUGAACCGGAUACUGCUUGAAGGGGUGCUGGGGACUUUGAGAGAGGGCGGCUGGCCCUGUCUGGUCGGGGAUGCUGGCCCAGACACAGGCCAUGGCUGGGAUGGGGUUCAGAAACAGGACCGCUGUCUCUCCCGGGCCAGGGCCCUCCCCAGCUGCUCCUGGCUUUCUGGUUCUUGGGGUCAGGGGCAGGCCUGUGCCAUGACCCCGCCACUGAGGCUGUGAGGAGGCUGUCGGUGCCCAAGGGCACCAAGGCACACCCCUACUCUUGCACCCCAUGUGUGGGCCCGAGCACCUGCUCUGCUGCCCCAAAGAUCUGGCGAUGUUUCCCAGGCAACUGUCUCUCACAGCCUGUCUGCCUGGCACUCCCGUAUCCCAUAAAUGCCACCACAUCUGGCUAUGGGUGGGCGUGCCUGCCUGGCAUCCACGGGCCAGCAGGUGUGGUGGAGCACAGCCCAGUUCCUGGCUGCGUCAGAAGGCUGCCCGGGCCUUUUGGCUGUCCUUGCCAGCAGCAAAACUCCGUCACCACAGCAGCAGAUGGCUCCGAAGAAGUGGAGCGUUUUCAUCAGGUUCAACUUUGAAACCUCCACCAUCACCAUCACCAGCACCGCUGUGUCAUGCUGAUAACUUGAGGACAGGCAGGACAAGGCCUUCUGGCGGCCGCCCCUGGUUUCUCCUGGGGGGUGAUGAGCGGGAGCGGCUCUGGGCCGAGCUACUGCGCACGGUGAGCCCGGAGCUGAUCCUGGAUCACGAGGUGCCUUCACUGCCCGCCUUCCCAGGACAGGAGCCCAGGUGCGGCCCGGAGCCCACUGAAGUCUUCACUGUCGGACCCAAGACCUUUUCCUGGACACCCUUUCCGCCGGACCUGUGGGGCCCGGGCCGUUCCUACCGGCUGCUUCACGGGGCAGGAGGGCACCUGGAAUCCCCCGCCAGGUCCCUGCCCCAGCGCCCGGCACCUGAUCCCUGCAGGGCCCCCAGGGUGGAGCAGCAGCCGUCUGUGGAGGGUGCCGCGGCCCUGCGCAGCUGCCCCAUGUGCCAGAAGGAGUUCGCCCCCAGGCUGACCCAGCUGGAUGUUGACAGCCACCUGGCCCAGUGCUUGGCCGAAAGCACAGAAGACGUGACGUGGUGAGCGCCAUCCAAGAGCCCUGCGCAGAGUGCGGCGCCCGGACACGCUCUCCCCCGCCAGCAGCCCCGCCUCUCGGCUCCCCCGCCAGCAGCCCCGCCUCUCGGCUCCCCCGCAUGCGCAUUAAAGCAGGGCGGGCUCCUGUCUGUCUCUGUGUUGUGAUGAAA